CUUUCACUUAGGCAUCGAUAGCACCCAUCAGAUGGCCAAAUCAUUAUUUACUGGACCAGGCCUUUUCAAAACUAUCAAGCAGAUAGUCAGGGCCUGUGAAGUGUGCCAGAGAAAUAAUCCCCUGCCUUAUCGCCAAGCUCCUUCAGGAGAACAAAGAACAGGCCAUUACCCUGGAGAAGACUGGCAACUGAUUUUACCCACAAGCCCAAACCUCAGGGAUUUCAGUAUCUACUAGUCUGGGUAGAUACUUUCACGGGUUGGGCAGAGGCCUUCCCCUGUAGGACAGAAAAGGCCCAAGAGGUAAUAAAGGCACUAGUUCAUGAAAUAAUUCCCAGAUUCGGACUUCCCCGAGGCUUACAGAGUGACAAUAGCCCUGCUUUCCAGGCCACAGUAACCCAGGGAGUAUCCCAGGCGUUAGGUAUACGAUAUCACUUACACUGCGCCUGAAGGCCACAGUCCUCAGGGAAGGUCGAGAAAAUGAAUGAAACACUCAAAGGACAUCUAAAAAAGCAAACCCAGGAAACCCACCUCACAUGGCCUGCUCUGUUGCCUAUAGCCUUAAAAAGAAUCUGCAACUUUCCCCAAAAAGCAGGACUUAGCCCAUACGAAAUGCUGUAUGGAAGGCCCUUCAUAACCAAUGACCUUGUGCUUGACCCAAGACAGCCAACUUAGUUGCAGACAUCACCUCCUUAGCCAAAUAUCAACAAGUUCUUAAAACAUUACAAGGAACCUAUCCCUGAGAAGAGGGAAAAGAACUAUUCCACCCUUGUGACAUGGUAUUAGUCAAGUCCCUUCCCUCUAAUUCCCCAUCCCUAGAUACAUCCUGGGAAGGACCCUACCCAGUCAUUUUAUCUACCCCAACUGCGGUUAAAGUGGCUGGAGUGGAGUCUUGGAUACAUCACACUUGAGUCAAAUCCUGGAUACUGCCAAAGGAACCUGAAAAUCCAGGAGACAACGCUAGCUAUUCCUGUGAACCUCUAGAGGAUUUGCGCCUGCUCUUCAAACAACAACCAGGAGGAAAGUAACUAAAAUCAUAAAUCCCCAUGGCCCUCCCUUAUCAUAUUUUUCUCUUUACUGUUCUUUUACCCUCUUUCACUCUCACUGCACCCCCUCCAUGCCGCUGUAUGACCAGUAGCUCCCCUUACCAAGAGUUUCUAUGGAGAAUGCAGCGUCCCGGAAAUAUUGAUGCCCCAUCGUAUAGGAGUCUUUCUAAGGGAACCCCCACCUUCACUGCCCACACCCAUAUGCCCCGCAACUGCUAUCACUCUGCCACUCUUUGCAUGCAUGCAAAUACUCAUUAUUGGACAGGAAAAAUGAUUAAUCCUAGUUGUCCUGGAGGACUUGGAGUCACUGUCUGUUGGACUUACUUCACCCAAACUGGUAUGUCUGAUGGGGGUGGAGUUCAAGAUCAGGCAAGAGAAAAACAUGUAAAAGAAGUAAUCUCCCAACUCACCCGGGUACAUGGCACCUCUAGCCCCUACAAAGGACUAGAUCUCUCAAAACUACAUGAAACCCUCCGUACCCAUACUCGCCUGGUAAGCCUAUUUAAUACCACCCUCACUGGGCUCCAUGAGGUCUCGGCCCAAAACCCUACUAACUGUUGGAUAUGCCUCCCCCUGAACUUCAGGCCAUAUGUUUCAAUCCCUGUACCUGAACAAUGGAACAACUUCAGCACAGAAAUAAACACCACUUCCGUUUUAGUAGGACCUCUUGUUUCCAAUCUGGAAAUAACCCAUACCUCAAACCUCACCUGUGUAAAAUUUAGCAAUACUACAUACACAACCAACUCCCAAUGCAUCAGGUGGGUAACUCCUCCCACACAAAUAGUCUGCCUACCCUCAGGAAUAUUUUUUGUCUGUGGUACCUCAGCCUAUCGUUGUUUGAAUGGCUCUUCAGAAUCUAUGUGCUUCCUCUCAUUCUUAGUGCCCCCUAUGACCAUCUACACUGAACAAGAUUUAUACAGUUAUGUCAUAUCUAAGCCCCGCAACAAAAGAGUACCCAUUCUUCCUUUUGUUAUAGGAGCAGGAGUGCUAGGUGCACUAGGUACUGGCAUUGGCGGUAUCACAACCUCUACUCAGUUCUACUACAAACUAUCUCAAGAACUAAAUGGGGACAUGGAACGGGUCGCCGACUCCCUGGUCACCUUGCAAGAUCAACUUAACUCCCUAGCAGCAGUAGUCCUUCAAAAUCGAAGAGCUUUAGACUUGCUAACCGCUGAAAGAGGGGGAACCUGUUUAUUUUUAGGGGAAGAAUGCUGUUAUUAUGUUAAUCAAUCCGGAAUCGUCACUGAGAAAGUUAAAGAAAUUCGAGAUCGAAUACAACGUAGAGCAGAGGAGCUUCGAAACACUGGACCCUGGGGCCUCCUCAGCCAAUGGAUGCCCUGGAUUCUCCCCUUCUUAGGACCUCUAGCAGCUAUAAUAUUGCUACUCCUCUUUGGACCCUGUAUCUUUAACCUCCUUGUUAACUUUGUCUCUUCCAGAAUCGAAGCUGUAAAACUACAAAUGGAGCCCAAGAUGCAGUCCAAGACUAAGAUCUACCGCAGACCCCUGGACCGGCCUGCUAGCCCACGAUCUGAUGUUAAUGACAUCAAAGGCACCCCUCCUGAGGAAAUCUCAGCUGCACAACCUCUACUACGCCCCAAUUCAGCAGGAAGCAGUUAGAGCGGUCGUCGGCCAACCUCCCCAACAGCACUUAGGUUUUCCUGUUGAGAUGGGGGACUGAGAGACAGGACUAGCUGGAUUUCCUAGGCUGACUAAGAAUCCCUAAGCCUAGCUGGGAAGGUGACCACAUCCACCUUUAAACACGGGGCUUGCAACUUAGCUCACACCUGACCAAUCAGAGAGCUCACUAAAAUGCUAAUUAGGCAAAGACAGGAGGUAAAGAAAUAGCCAAUCAUCUAUUGCCUGAGAGCACAGCAGGAGGGACAAUGAUCGGGAUAUAAACCCAAGUCUUCGAGCCGGCAACGGCAACCCCCUUUGGGUCCCCUCCCUUUGUAUGGGAGCUCUGUUUUCAUGCUAUUUCACUCUAUUAAAUCUUGCAACUGCA